AGCGGUGCUCGGGUCCGGUAACAACAUGGCGGCGUCCGUGAGGGGCUCCUUUGGGCAGGGGUAGUGUUUGGUGUCCCUGUCUUGCGUGAUAUUGACAAACUGAAGCUUUCCUGCACCACUGGACUUAAGGAAGAGUGUACUCGUAGGCGGACAGCUUUAGUGGCCGGCCGGCCGCUCUCAUCCCCCGUAAGGAGCAGAGUCCUUUGUACUGACCAAGAUGAGCAACAUCUACAUCCAGGAGCCUCCCACGAAUGGGAAGGUUUUAUUGAAAACUACAGCUGGAGAUAUUGACAUAGAGUUGUGGUCCAAAGAAGCUCCUAAAGCUUGCAGAAAUUUUAUCCAACUUUGUUUGGAAGCUUAUUAUGACAAUACCAUUUUUCAUAGAGUUGUGCCUGGUUUCAUAGUCCAAGGCGGAGAUCCUACUGGCACAGGGAGUGGUGGAGAGUCUAUCUAUGGAGCGCCAUUCAAAGAUGAAUUUCAUUCACGGUUGCGUUUUAAUCGGAGAGGACUGGUUGCCAUGGCAAAUGCUGGUUCUCAUGAUAAUGGCAGCCAGUUUUUCUUCACACUGGGUCGAGCAGAUGAACUUAACAAUAAGCAUACCAUCUUUGGAAAGGUUACAGGGGAUACAGUAUAUAACAUGUUGCGACUGUCAGAAGUAGACAUUGAUGAUGACGAAAGACCACAUAAUCCACACAAAAUAAAAAGCUGUGAGGUUUUGUUUAAUCCUUUUGAUGACAUCAUUCCAAGGGAAAUUAAAAGGCUGAAAAAAGAGAAACCAGAGGAGGAAGUAAAGAAAUUGAAACCCAAAGGCACAAAAAAUUUUAGUUUACUUUCAUUUGGAGAGGAAGCUGAGGAAGAAGAGGAGGAAGUAAAUCGAGUUAGUCAGAGCAUGAAGGGCAAAAGCAAAAGUAGUCAUGACUUGCUUAAGGAUGAUCCACAUCUCAGUUCUGUUCCAGUUGUAGAAAGUGAAAAAGGUGAUGCACCAGAUUUAGUUGAUGAUGGAGAAGAUGAAAGUGCAGAGCAUGAUGAAUAUAUUGAUGGUGAUGAAAAGAACCUGAUGAGAGAAAGAAUUGCCAAAAAAUUAAAAAAGGACACAAGUGCGAAUGUUAAAUCAGCUGGAGAAGGAGAAGUGGAGAAGAAAUCAGUCAGCCGCAGGAAAUUACUCUGCCUAACCUUGGAGCCCAGCCUACAGCCCGGCCCAACUGCAGAUCUCAAAUAGCAGAAUUGCCCAUCCAGGGAAUACAACUUGCAACUGGCCUGAUGAGAAGCCAUCACAGUUUCUAGCCAUUAACUCUGCCUAAUAGCAGAGCCCAGCCACUGAUCUCACCAGACAGUGGAGUCUAUCCAGCAGCCCCAUGUAACAUCAGAGGAAAGGCAUCUGCCCAGCAAAUUAGAGAACUCCCAACAAGCUCUGACUCCCUGGGAUCAUCACCAGCUGGCCCUUCCCAGGCUAAACUAAAUAGUGAACCUCUAUCCAUGCCAAAGAACACCUAUUGUAAAGGCUAGAAGAGGGGGCUUUCUCCUCAAAUGCAUAGACAAUAACACAAGGACACAAGAACUACAAAGAACAAAAGAAAUCCCAAAAGAAACUAAUAAAGCUUCAGUAAUGGACCCCAAAGAAACGGAGAUAUUUGGAAUGACUGAGGAAGAAUUUAGAAUACUACUCAUAAAGAUGUUCAGUGAUGUACAAGAAUAUAUGGAUAGAAAAUGUAAUAAAAUUUGGAAACUGAUACCUAACAAAAAUAACAAGUUUGACAGAAAUAGAAACAAUAUAAAAGAAACACAUAUAAAUUCUAGAGUUGAGGAAUACAAUGACUGAACUGAAAAAUUCAAUAGAAAGCAUCAUUGGUGGAUUUGAUAGAGCAGAAGAAAGAAUCAAUGAGCUGGAAGACAGCAUUUGAUAUUAUCCAGUUAGAGGACCAGAAAGACAAAAGAGUGAAAAAGAAUGAAGAAAGCUUAUGGGACUUAUGAGACACCAUCAAGAGUUCAAACCUUUGCAUACUAGGAUUUGCAAAAGAAGAAAGAGAAAAAGGGUCACAAAGCCUAUUUAAGGAAAGAAUGACUGAAAAAUCCCCUAAUCUGGGAAUAGAUGUGAAUAUCCAGGUACAAGAAGCACAGAAAUUUCAAUCAAAUUCAACACACAGAGGAGUACACCAAGGCAUACAAUAAUCUAGCUGUCAAAAAUCAAAGACAAAACAUUUUGAGAACAGCAAGAGAUAAUAAACACAUCACAUACAAAGGAGACAAUAUGACUAUCAGCAGAUUUCCCAGCAGAAACCCAGUAGGCCAGGAGAGAGUGGCAUAAUAUAAUUGAAAUGCCGGAGGAAAACAAACACAAAAACUACCAAUCAAGAAUACUUAACCCAGCAAAGCUAUCUUUCAUAAUUGAGAAGGAAAUAAUACUUUCUCCCUCAGUUUCAUGAAACAUAUGAAUUGCAAAACUCAAUGGUAUAUGUAAAAUAGUGCCAUAUUCAGAAAACUGUAGGACUGUAAUAAUGGUGCAUAAGGCAAUUUCAUCCCUAGUACAUGAGUCAAAAAACAAAAAUAUUAAUAGCAGCUAUAGCUAAAAUAAAUUAUCAAGGUAUACACAUUAAAAAUGAUGUAAAUUCUGCCAUUAAAAACAUAAUGUUGAGGGGGUAUGAAAAAGUAUAGAAUUGUUGUAUGCAAAGUUAAUUGUUGUAUGCAAAGUUAAGUUGUUAUCAGCUUAUACUUGAUUGUUUAUAAGCUGUUAUCAGUUUAUACUUGAUUGUUUAUAAGAUGUUCUGUGUAAACCUCAUGGUAAUCACAAAGCAAAAAUCUUUAGUGGAAAUAUAAAGCAAAAAUAGAAAGGAUUCAAAGCAUACCACUAUAGAAAACCAUCAAAUCACAAAGGAAGACAGCAAGGGAGGAAGACAAAAAAAAUUAUUUACCAAACAUCCAGAAAAAAA